AGUCCCGCUCCGCGCCGCGCCGCUCCGCUCCGGCUCGGGCUCCGGCUCGCCUCGGGCUGGGCUCGGGCUCCGGGGGCGGCGUCCCCCGCGCCGGGCCCCGGGACGGGCGGCGACGCUCCAACCAUGGCCCGUGCCCAGGCGCUCGUGCUGGCACUCACCUUCCAGCUCUGCGCGCCGGAGACCGAGACUCCGGCAGCUGGCUGCACCUUCGAGGAGGCAAGUGACCCAGCAGUGCCCUGCGAGUACAGCCAGGCCCAGUACGAUGACUUCCAGUGGGAGCAAGUGCGAAUCCACCCUGGCACCCGGGCACCUGCGGACCUGCCCCACGGCUCCUACUUGAUGGUCAACACUUCCCAGCAUGCCCCAGGCCAGCGAGCCCAUGUCAUCUUCCAGAGCCUGAGCGAGAAUGAUACCCACUGUGUGCAGUUCAGCUACUUCCUGUACAGCCGGGACGGGCACAGCCCGGGCACCCUGGGCGUCUACGUGCGCGUUAAUGGGGGCCCCCUGGGCAGUGCUGUGUGGAAUAUGACUGGAUCCCACGGCCGUCAGUGGCACCAGGCUGAGCUGGCUGUCAGCACUUUCUGGCCCAAUGAAUAUCAGGUGCUGUUUGAGGCCCUCAUCUCCCCAGACCGCAGGGGCUACAUGGGCCUAGAUGACAUCCUGCUUCUCAGCUACCCCUGCGCAAAGGCCCCACACUUCUCCCGCCUGGGCGACGUGGAGGUCAACGCGGGCCAGAACGCGUCGUUCCAGUGCAUGGCCGCGGGCAGAGCGGCCGAGGCCGAACGCUUCCUCUUGCAACGGCAGAGCGGGGCGCUGGUGCCGGCGGCGGGCGUGCGGCACAUCAGCCACCGGCGCUUCCUGGCCACUUUCCCGCUGGCUGCCGUGAGCCGCGCCGAGCAGGACCUGUACCGCUGUGUGUCCCAGGCCCCGCGCGGCGCGGGCGUCUCUAACUUCGCGGAGCUCAUCGUCAAGGAGCCCCCAACUCCCAUCGCGCCCCCACAGCUGCUGCGUGCUGGCCCCACCUACCUCAUCAUCCAGCUCAACACCAACUCCAUCAUUGGCGACGGGCCGAUCGUGCGCAAGGAGAUUGAGUACCGCAUGGCGCGCGGGCCCUGGGCUGAGGUGCACGCCGUCAGCCUGCAGACCUACAAGCUGUGGCACCUCGACCCCGACACAGAGUAUGAGAUCAGCGUGCUGCUCACGCGUCCCGGAGACGGCGGCACUGGCCGCCCUGGGCCACCCCUCAUCAGCCGCACCAAAUGCGCAGAGCCCAUGAGGGCCCCCAAAGGCCUGGCUUUUGCUGAGAUCCAGGCCCGUCAGCUGACCCUGCAGUGGGAACCACUGGGCUACAACGUGACGCGUUGCCACACCUAUACUGUGUCGCUGUGCUAUCACUACACCCUGGGCAGCAGCCACAACCAGACCAUCCGAGAGUGUGUGAAGACAGAGCAAGGUGUCAGCCGCUACACCAUCAAGAACCUGCUGCCCUAUCGGAACGUUCACGUGAGGCUUGUCCUCACUAACCCUGAGGGGCGCAAAGAGGGCAAGGAGGUCACUUUCCAGACGGAUGAGGAUGUGCCCAGUGGGAUUGCAGCCGAGUCCCUGACCUUCACUCCACUGGAGGACAUGAUCUUCCUCAAGUGGGAGGAGCCCCAGGAGCCCAAUGGUCUCAUCACCCAGUAUGAGAUCAGCUACCAGAGCAUCGAGUCAUCAGACCCGGCAGUGAACGUGCCAGGCCCACGACGUACCAUCUCCAAGCUCCGCAAUGAGACCUACCAUGUCUUCUCCAACCUGCACCCAGGCACCACCUACCUGUUCUCCGUGCGGGCCCGCACAGGCAAAGGCUUCGGCCAGGCGGCACUCACUGAGAUAACCACUAACAUCUCUGCUCCCAGCUUUGAUUAUGCCGACAUGCCGUCACCCCUGGGCGAGUCUGAGAACACCAUCACCGUGCUGCUGAGGCCGGCACAGGGCCGCGGUGCGCCCAUCAGUGUGUACCAGGUGAUUGUGGAGGAGGAGCGGGCGCGGAGGCUGCGGCGGGAGCCAGGUGGACAGGACUGCUUCCCAGUGCCAUUGACCUUCGAGGCGGCGCUGGCCCGAGGCCUGGUGCACUACUUCGGGGCCGAACUGGCGGCCAGCAGUCUACCUGAGGCCAUGCCCUUUACCGUGGGUGACAACCAGACCUACCGAGGCUUCUGGAACCCACCACUUGAGCCUAGGAAGGCCUAUCUCAUCUACUUCCAGGCAGCAAGCCACCUGAAGGGGGAGACCCGGCUGAAUUGCAUCCGCAUUGCCAGGAAAGCUGCCUGCAAGGAAAGCAAGCGGCCCCUGGAGGUGUCCCAGAGAUCGGAGGAGAUGGGGCUUAUCCUGGGCAUCUGUGCAGGGGGGCUUGCUGUCCUCAUCCUUCUCCUGGGUGCCAUCAUUGUCAUCAUCCGCAAAGGGAGAGACCACUAUGCCUACUCCUACUACCCGAAGCCGGUGAACAUGACCAAGGCCACCGUCAACUACCGCCAGGAGAAGACACACAUGAUGAGCGCCGUGGACCGCAGCUUCACAGACCAGAGCACCCUGCAGGAGGACGAGCGGCUGGGCCUGUCCUUCAUGGACACCCAUGGCUACAGCACCCGGGGAGACCAGCGCAGCGGUGGGGUCACUGAGGCCAGCAGCCUCCUGGGGGGCUCCCCGAGGCGUCCCUGUGGCCGGAAGGGCUCCCCAUACCACACGGGGCAGCUGCACCCUGCGGUGCGUGUCGCAGACCUUCUGCAGCACAUCAACCAGAUGAAGACGGCCGAGGGUUACGGCUUCAAGCAGGAGUAUGAGAGCUUCUUUGAAGGCUGGGACGCCACAAAGAAGAAAGACAAGGUCAAGGGCAGCCGGCAGGAGCCAAUGCCUGCCUAUGAUCGGCACCGAGUGAAACUGCACCCGAUGCUGGGAGACCCCAAUGCCGACUACAUUAAUGCCAACUACAUAGAUGGUUACCACAGGUCAAACCACUUCAUAGCCACUCAAGGGCCGAAGCCUGAGAUGGUCUAUGACUUCUGGCGUAUGGUGUGGCAGGAGCACUGUUCCAGCAUCGUCAUGAUCACCAAGCUGGUCGAGGUGGGCAGGGUGAAAUGCUCACGGUACUGGCCGGAGGACUCAGACACCUACGGGGACAUCAAGAUUAUGCUGGUGAAGACAGAGACCCUGGCUGAGUAUGUCGUGCGCACUUUUGCCCUGGAGCGGAGAGGCUACUCUGCCCGGCACGAGGUCCGCCAGUUCCACUUCACAGCGUGGCCAGAGCAUGGCGUCCCCUACCAUGCCACGGGGCUGCUGGCUUUCAUCCGGCGCGUGAAGGCCUCCACCCCACCUGAUGCCGGGCCCAUUGUCAUCCACUGCAGCGCGGGCACCGGCCGCACAGGUUGCUAUAUCGUCCUGGAUGUGAUGCUGGACAUGGCAGAGUGUGAGGGCGUCGUGGACAUUUACAACUGUGUGAAGACUCUCUGCUCCCGGCGUGUCAACAUGAUCCAGACUGAGGAGCAGUACAUCUUCAUUCAUGAUGCAAUCCUGGAGGCCUGCCUGUGUGGGGAGACCACCAUCCCUGUCAGUGAGUUCAAGGCCACCUACAAGGAGAUGAUCCGCAUUGAUCCUCAGAGUAAUUCCUCCCAGCUGCGGGAAGAGUUCCAGACGCUGAACUCGGUCACCCCGCCGCUGGACGUGGAGGAGUGCAGCAUCGCCCUGUUGCCCCGGAACCGCGACAAGAACCGCAGCAUGGACGUCCUGCCGCCCGACCGCUGCCUGCCCUUCCUCAUCUCCACUGAUGGGGACUCCAACAACUACAUUAAUGCAGCCCUGACUGACAGCUACACACGGAGUGCGGCCUUCAUCGUGACCCUGCACCCGCUGCAGAGCACCACGCCCGACUUCUGGCGGCUGGUCUACGAUUACGGGUGCACCUCCAUCGUCAUGCUCAACCAGCUGAACCAGUCCAACUCCGCCUGGCCCUGCCUGCAGUACUGGCCAGAGCCAGGCCGGCAGCAAUAUGGCCUCAUGGAGGUGGAGUUUAUGUCGGGCACAGCUGAUGAAGACUUAGUGGCUCGAGUCUUCCGGGUGCAGAACAUCUCUCGGUUGCAGGAGGGGCACCUGCUGGUGCGGCACUUCCAGUUCCUGCGCUGGUCUGCAUACCGGGACACACCUGACUCCAAGAAGGCCUUCUUGCACCUGCUGGCUGAGGUGGACAAGUGGCAGGCCGAGAGUGGGGAUGGGCGCACCAUCGUGCACUGCCUAAACGGGGGAGGACGCAGCGGCACCUUCUGCGCCUGCGCCACGGUCCUGGAGAUGAUCCGCUGCCACAACUUGGUGGACGUUUUCUUUGCUGCCAAAACCCUCCGGAACUACAAACCCAACAUGGUGGAGACCAUGGAUCAGUACCACUUUUGCUACGAUGUGGCCCUGGAGUACUUGGAGGGGCUGGAGUCAAGAUAGCGGGGCCCUGGCCUGGGGCACCCACUGCACACUCAGGGCCAGACCCACCAUCCUGGACUGGCGAGGAAGAUCAGUGCCUCCUGCUCUGCCCAAACACACUCCCAUGGGGCAAGCACUGGAGUGGAUGCUGGGCUAUCUUGCUCCCCCUUCCACUGUGGGCAGGGCCUUUCGCUUGUCCCAUGGGCGGGUGGUGGGCCAAGGAGGAGCUUAGCAAGUCUGCAGCCCAGCCCCACCUCCAUAGGGUCCUGCAGGCCUGUGCUGAGAGGCCUGGUGCUGCCUGGCAGAGUGACAAAGGCUCAGGACGGCUGGCUCUGGGGGACUCAGGCCAAGCCCCUUGGCACCAUCCUGGCUUUUGGCAGGGAUGAGUGAGGCCCUGCAGAGAGCAUCCCAGGCCAAGGUUCCCACUCAGCCUGCCCCCUCUGCAUGUGGGUAGAGGAUGUACUGGGACUUGGCAUUUAGGAUUCCAUCUGGCCCAGCCCCUGAAGGUCCUGGGGAAGCAGGUCUCAAUUCUGAAUAGCCAGUGGGGCACACUGACUGUCCUCCCCAGGGGAACUGCAGCGCCCUCCUCCCCACUGCCCCCUGCAGCCCCUGAGAUAUUUUGCUCACUAUCCCUCCCCACUUGCUUCCCUGAUAUGUGCUCUGAGCUUCCCUGAACCAGGAUCUGCCUAUUACUGCUGUGCCCCAUGGGGGGCUCCUUCCCUGCCUGACCCACUGUUGCAGAAUGAAGUCACCUCGCCCCCCUCUUCCUUUAAUCUUCAGGCCUCACUGGCCUGUCCUGCUCAGCUUGGGCCAGUGACAAUCUGCAAGGCUGAACAACAGCCCCUGGGGUUGAGGCCCCUGUGGCUCCUGGUCAGGCUGCCCGUUGUGGGGAGGGGCAGUGUUAGAGCAGGGCUGGUCAUACCCUCUGGAGUUCAGAGGAAGAGGUAGGACCAGUGCUUUUUUGUUUCUUUUGUUAUUUUUGGUUGGGUGGGUGGGAAGGUCUCUUUAAAAUGGGGCAGGCCACACCCCCAUUCCGUGCCUCAAUUUCCCCAUCUGUAAACUGUAGAUAUGACUACUGACCUACCUCGCAGGGGGCUGUGGGGAGGCAUAAGCUGAUGUUUGUAAAGCGCUUUGUAAAUAAACGUGCUCUCUGAAUGCCA